AAACCUGUUGCCGUCUGACUGCCACGUGGCUCACUAUUUAUCCCUGUAAAAAUCUGCAAAAGUAUUUGAAAGGGAAGAAGGGACAGAAAACUCCCUCCUUUUCCAAGUUAGCCUUAUAGUCUAGGGCUUAAAAUACUGGUUUAAUGGUGAAGGUAAGUGCUUUUCUUCUUUUUGGGUAGAAGGAUUAUUACUAACUUACCAAAGGUCCAUUAAGGGGAGGGAACAGUUUUAGGAGAAGUCAGAGAAAAGACAUUAACAGCAACAUAAGGAUCUCCAUCUGGUAAUAUUGCCUAAUUCCAAAAUGAAGAGACUCUCUGAAAAAGAUAACUGAUUCAAUGAAGACCCUAGGGCAAGGCUUGAGAAGCCACUGGUACCAAUGGACACUGUGGACAAUGGUCAUUUCUCCAAGGACGCUAUAAAAGACUGUCGUAGUAAAAGAGAUUCAGGGCACAGGGAAACUCCACCACAAAGCGUGGUACCAUUUCCCACAGAAGCUAAAUGGACGGGAAGCCUGCCACCAGGAAAGGUCCAGAUUUCUGUUCAUUACGCUAUGGGCUGGCUCUUAUCAUGCACUUCUCAAACUUCACCAUGAUAACGCAGCGUGUGAGUCUGAGCAUUGCGAUCAUCGCCAUGGUGAACACCACUCAGCAGCAAGGUCUAUCUAAUGCCUCCACUGAGGGGCCUGUUGCAGAUGCCUUCAAUAACUCCAGCAUAUCCAUCAAGGAAUUUGAUACAAAGGCCUCUGUGUAUCAAUGGAGCCCAGAAACUCAGGGUAUCAUCUUUAGCUCCAUCAACUAUGGGAUAAUACUGACUCUGAUCCCAAGUGGAUAUUUAGCAGGGAUAUUUGGAGCAAAAAAAAUGCUUGGUGCUGGUUUGCUGAUCUCUUCCCUUCUCACCCUCUUUACACCACUGGCUGCUGACUUCGGAGUGAUUUUGGUCAUCAUGGUUCGGACAGUCCAGGGCAUGGCCCAGGGAAUGGCAUGGACAGGUCAGUUUACUAUUUGGGCAAAGUGGGCUCCUCCACUUGAACGAAGCAAGCUCACCACCAUUGCAGGAUCAGGGUCAGCAUUUGGAUCCUUCAUCAUCCUCUGUGUGGGGGGACUAAUCUCACAGGCCUUGAGCUGGCCUUUUAUCUUCUACAUCUUUGGUAGCACUGGCUGUGUCUGCUGUCUCCUAUGGUUCACAGUGAUUUAUGAUGACCCCAUGCAUCACCCGUGCAUAAGUGUUAGGGAAAAGGAGCACAUCCUGUCCUCACUGGCUCAACAGCCCAGUUCUCCUGGACGAGCUGUCCCCAUAAAGGCGAUGGUCACAUGCCUACCACUUUGGGCCAUUUUCCUGGGUUUUUUCAGCCAUUUCUGGUUGUGCACCAUCAUCCUAACAUACCUACCAACGUAUAUCAGUACUCUGCUCCAUGUUAACAUCAGAGAUAGUGGAGUUCUGUCCUCCCUGCCUUUUAUUGCUGCUGCAAGCUGUACAAUUUUAGGAGGUCAGCUGGCAGAUUUCCUUUUGUCCAGGAAUCUUCUCAGAUUGAUCACUGUGCGAAAGCUCUUUUCAUCUCUUGGGCUCCUCCUUCCAUCAAUAUGUGCUGUGGCCCUGCCCUUUGUGGCCUCCAGUUACGUGAUAACCAUUAUUUUGCUGAUACUUAUUCCUGGGACCAGUAACCUAUGUGACUCAGGGUUUAUCAUCAACACCUUAGAUAUCGCCCCCAGAUAUGCAAGUUUCCUCAUGGGAAUCUCAAGGGGAUUUGGGCUCAUCGCAGGAAUCAUCUCUUCCACUGCCACUGGAUUCCUCAUCAGUCAGGUUGGGCCAGUUUAUUGAACAUCUUCAAGUGGCAGGAUUUUGAGUCUGGUUGGAGGAAUGUCUUUUUCCUGUCUGCUGCAGUCAACAUGUUUGGCCUGGUCUUUUACCUCACGUUUGGACAAGCAGAACUUCAAGACUGGGCCAAAGAGAGGACCCUUACCCGCCUCUGAGGACAUAAAGUUACAAACUUAAAUGUGGUACUGAGCAUGAACUUUUUAAACAUUUUUUACUUCUCUCCAUAUUCCUGACCAUAGACUCAGCAGUUCUUAACUCUGGCUGUGUGUUAGUCUUCCCUGGGGAGCCUUUAUAAGACACUGAUACUUGGGACCCACUCCAGAGAUUCUGAAUGAAUUGGUCUGGGGUGGAACCCAGAUACUACUAAUUUUUAGAUACUCCUUAGAGGUUUCUAGCAUGCGCCCGGGGUUGACAACAGCUGGACAAACUUGAAAAGUCAAUUCAUGUGGCCUUUGAAUUUUCCUCAUUGGAAAGUACUAAAUAAAUAAAAAUUCAUGUGAAAAUGAUCACUGAUAAAUAUCUUCAUGGUGGGGCAGGUUAUUGGAUGCAGAGAAGAUCUGCUCGGAAUUGUAGCCAUAUGUUACAGAUCUCAGCACCGAUCGGAACUGUAAAGCUAUAAUCCCCAGAAUUAAAGUUUUUAUUAUUUUUUAUACAUUGUAAAACAUAGACGUUUAUUUAUGUGAUUAAAUUCUAUUAAAAUUUACAUGCUAAAAUAAAA